CCCAAAGCGCUGGGAUUACAGGCGUGAGCUGCUGCACCCGGCCACUCCCAGGAUUUUUAAUUUGUUCAGUGAGGUGGGCCAGCUACACCCAAGGCUGAUGAAGCGCCUAAGCUUUGGAAAAUGAAAAGAUAGGCAGCCAGAGGUUCUCUGCCUGGAAUUUGUCUCCACGUGGCUCCCCACUGGUCACACCUGGACAUUAACCUUCUCUUCACCUGGAUCUCUGUUCUUUCUGAGGCCAAACACUUCCUCCUGCUGUUCUGUGGCUCCAGCUGAGGUUGUGGCCUCCUGCCCUUCCCCCACCCCUCAUGUAAGGGCUCAGGAACUCGUUUCUCUUACUCAAUAUUCAGGGUUUUCCUUCCUCAGGGGUGGGGAGUGGGGGUAGGGUGGCAGGGAUUUCCAAGGCUGCCUUUCUUGCAGGGAUGGGUGCCCCUGCCCACACCUUGGAGCCUGUUCUGGAAUUUCGACCCGUCUUGAUGUGCAGGAGGGGAGUGGCAAAGUCUAGUCGUGAGUCCUAUCCAGCAGCCAAGGCCUGGUGGAGCCAGCUGCUGUGUGAUCCCAGGUUCUGCCUUGACCCUCUCUGGGAGGAAGCUGAGUUCCACUGGACACCUACUCAAGAUCUAUUUAGCCCCCAGCCACACUGUGGGAUUUUAAACCCAUGUUUGAUGUGAAAUGGACUGAGAGAGGGCAGGUGAUUUACCUGAGUGGUGGGAGCAUUGAGAUGGAGAGUACCUUAGUGACAGCAGUUAGGUGGGGAAUGAGGUGGGGAAUUCCACUCCCUUGCCCUGACCCUUCCAUUUUCAUGACCUAAGGCUGAGGCUCUCCUCUAGGUGGGGUUACCUGUGUUUGGGCUCCCAAUUACUGGGCUAAAUUCUAGGACCUGCCAUUCCCUUGAGCCCCUAGCCCCUGGCUUGUCUCCUGGCCUCAUUUGAAUACGGGUCCCACCUCAAGGCUGGACACAUUUCAGGCUCUGCCCCUGCUUCCGUUCCAUGUCAUUGGCCCCACCCCAUUCUCUGGGUCACCUCCCCCUUAACCCUGUUCAGCCCCAGACGUGCCUCUGGCCAGCACGUGCUUGCCAGAAGUCAGGAGGGCCAACCUUGAGGCUGAAGGGAUCUGCGCUGGCGCAGUGCACUUGGCGGGAACCAUGAGGCAGAGGCUCGCGCCUCCAGAGCCUCCCUGAGCGCAUGCGCCGUGGAGCUCCCUUGAGCUAGUCAAGAGUGCGGGCGAGGCGCGGGGGGUGAGGGACUGACCCUCGGGGCCCGGAGGUGGGUCAGAUCUGAGCCCGGAGGACAACCCUGGGAGCAUCGGGUAGAGAAACAGGAUCGUGUGGGGACAGGGCGUGGGGCCACAGGAGAUCGGAGCCCAUGGGAGAUGUGGGAGGCCGGCGUGGCCCCACGGAGGAGCGGAACCUUGGGUUGGCCUGUGCGGGCUGAGGAGGAGUUCAACAGAGUGACGGGGUAUUCUGGGCAGGGGACAGCCUUUGCUGGAAUUUUUCAGCCCUUGCGAAGGCCUCGGGACGUGCCUGAAUGGGAUGUAGUAAGACGGACAGAGUCAGAGGUUCUCGACUGGACCGGGUUGGUGGCCUGAAUGUAUUAGCUUCGCUGCGUCUGCCCAAGAGAAAUAAGAAUGUCUAAGCCCCUGGAGGCCGAGAAGCAAGGUCUGGACUCCCCAUCAGAGCACACAGACACCGAAAGAAAUGGACCAGACACUAAUCAUCAGAACCCCCAAAAUAAGACCUCCCCAUUCUCCGUGUCCCCAACUGGCCCCAGUACAAAGGUGGGCAUUCUCUCUGGCCUCCACUUAACAUUCUGGGGUCCCGGACCCUGCCUCUCUCCCCCCCAGAUCAAGGCUGAAGACCCCAGUGGCGAUUCAGCCCCAGCAGCACCCCUGCCCCCUCAGCCGGCCCAGCCUCAUCUGCCCCAGGCCCAACUCAUGUUGACGGGCAGCCAGCUAGCUGGGCUCACGGCACUGAUGCCAGCUCAGCAGCAGCUCCUCCUGCAGCAAGCCCAGGCCCAGCUCCUGGCCGCCGCCGUGCAGCAGUCCAGUGCCGCCGCUGCCGCUAACGCCGCUGCCGCCGCCGCCGCCGCCUCCGCCUCCUCCUCUACUUCCUCCUCCUCCUCCUCCUCUGCCUCCUCCUCGACCUCACAGCCCCCAGCCUCCUCUGGGGGGGGUGACCUGCCACCACCACAGCCUGCCAGCCAGCCCCCUGGGACCCCACAGCUCACCUUGUCCCAACCCAUCCAGCUCACAGCACAGGACAUACAGCAGCUCCUCCAGCUCCAGCAGCUGGUGCUUGUGCCAGGCCACCACCUCCAGCCACCUGCUCAGUUCCUGCUACCGCAGGCCCAGCAGAGCCAGCCAGGCCUGCUACCGACACCAAAUCUAUUCCAGCUACCUCAGCAAACCCAGGGAGCUCUUCUGACCUCCCAGCCCCGGGCCGGGCUUCCCACACAGCCCCCCAAAUGCUUGGAGCCACCAUCCCACCCCGAGGAGCCCAGUGAUCUGGAGGAGCUGGAGCAAUUCGCCCGCACCUUCAAGCAACGCCGCAUCAAGCUGGGCUUCACGCAGGGUGAUGUGGGCCUGGCCAUGGGCAAGCUCUACGGCAACGACUUCAGCCAGACGACCAUUUCCCGCUUCGAGGCCCUCAACCUGAGCUUCAAGAACAUGUGCAAACUCAAGCCCCUCCUGGAGAAGUGGCUCAACGAUGCAGAGACUAUGUCUGUGGACUCAAGCCUGCCCAGCCCCAACCAGCUGAGCAGCCCCAGCCUGGGUUUCGACGGCCUGCCCGGCCGGAGACGCAAGAAGAGGACCAGCAUCGAGACAAACGUCCGCUUCGCCUUAGAGAAGAGUUUUCUAGCGAACCAGAAGCCUACCUCAGAGGAGAUCCUGCUGAUCGCCGAGCAGCUGCACAUGGAGAAGGAAGUGAUCCGCGUCUGGUUCUGCAACCGGCGCCAGAAGGAGAAACGCAUCAACCCCUGCAGUGCGGCCCCCAUGCUGCCCAGCCCAGGGAAGCCGGCCAGCUACAGCCCCCAUAUGGUCACACCCCAAGGGGGCGCGGGGACCUUACCGUUGUCCCAAGCUUCCAGCAGUCUGAGCACAACAGUUACUACCUUAUCCUCAGCUGUGGGGACGCUCCACCCCAGCCGGACAGCUGGAGGGGGUGGGGGCGGGGGCGGGGCUGCGCCCCCCCUCAAUUCCAUCCCCUCUGUCACUCCCCCACCCCCGGCCACCACCAACAGCACAAACCCCAGCCCUCAAGGCAGCCACUCGGCUAUCGGCUUGUCAGGCCUGAACCCCAGCACGGGAAGCACAAUGGUGGGGUUGAGCUCCGGGCUGAGUCCAGCCCUCAUGAGCAACAACCCUUUGGCCACUAUCCAAGCCCUGGCCUCUGGUGGAACCCUGCCCCUUACCAGCCUUGAUGGCAGCGGGAAUCUGGUGCUGGGGGCAGCCGGUGCAGCCCCGGGGAGCCCUGGCCUGGUGACCUCGCCGCUCUUCUUGAAUCAUGCUGGGCUGCCCCUGCUCAGCACCCCGCCUGGUGUGGGCCUGGUCUCAGCAGCGGCUGCGGCUGUGGCAGCCUCCAUCUCCAGCAAGUCUCCUGGCCUCUCCUCCUCAUCCUCUUCAUCCUCAUCCUCCUCCUCCUCCACUUGCAGCGAGACGGCAGCACAGACCCCUGGAGGUCCAGGGGGGCCCGAGGCAGGGUCCAAACCUGAGUGAGGGCCAGCCAUGCCUCCCCUCCCAUUCCUCUGGUCCCUGCCUUGGUCCCUUGCCUGGGAAGAGGGCGAGGAGGCCAGUGGUGGGGACGCAGAGGGUCCUCAGAGCAGGAGUGACAAGGGAGGAAAGACCAAAAAAACAACCAACCAAAAAAAAAAAAAAAAAGGAAAGAAACUAACCAACAAAAGAGAAAACCAAAAAUAAUCACAACAGAAACCAGCUGCCCCAAAGGAACCAGAGGUGAAAAACAAACAAAAAAAAACCAAAAACAAACCAAAAAAAAAAAAAACCCACAAAAUCAAACAAACCAAAAAACCAGUCGCGAGCCAGACCUCAGCGUGCUCACCCUCACUGCUACGACGCCAAAUAAAAACCCCAGCCAGGGGCGGAGAAGCCUCCAGCAGGUCAGACCUCAUGCCACCGAGCCCUGGCUGUGGGACCAACCCCCAACCCUGCCUCCCCCGUGGGGGCUACAGAAGGAAAAAGAGAAGAUGCCAGCUUCCUAAUCCCAGCCCCCAGCCCUGGGCCAGCGAAGACAGGGCACAGCCUGGGCAGAUGGGCUGGGGCUUAGCACCACCCACCAAAUGUUCUUUUCCAGAAGGUGAAAGAGAAAGGGCCUGAACAACCUUACACCAAAUAUUCAGUAGCUUCAUCCAAAGGAUGUACAGAAUUUUUAGCAUUGUGCUCAACAGAAUGUGUCCCUACCAUGUGUCCCCUUCUCCCCUGGCCCCCAGCUCUCCCCACCUGGGCAGGGGGUCUUGCUUUAACCUCCUCCCUCCCCCCAGCAGGGGAGAGUUCAAGGGAAGGCCUGCGGACAACUUUUCAUCCCCUGUUCCUCCCUCUUUUCCCCUUUGAAGGGUGGGCUAGGCCAUUUUGCCAAGUUCUAGCUCUCACAAGUCCCUCCUCAACCCUGUCACCCUCCUCUGCUCUGGAACUGACUCCCUCCCCAGCCUAUGGGAAGGUGGAAAUUUCAGGCAAGAGGGGAUGAAGACAUUCAGUUGAGGGCAUUCAGUUGUCUUUUUCCAUCCUGUCUGUUUCCCUGAAAAAAAAAAAAAUUCAUAUUCCAGUGCCUAUCCGUGGGAUCCUUCACGUUCUUUGACAUUAACCAGAAACCAAAAAGAGAACUCACCUCGCUUUUCCCACCCUGUGCCCCUCUGGUACUGGCGAAUGCCUCUCCCUCCCCCCACAUGCACGCACGCACACACCCCAGUGGUGGGGUUCCUCGAGAUGGCAUCCCCAUCAGGGUCCAUGUGGUGGGGACAGUGCCACAGCCUGUGGUCCCCAUCUGAGAGGGCGCGGUGGUGGCCACCACUCCCACAAGACCUCCACAACUCUUGGCUGGACCCUGUGUUUGACCAGCCCCGGACACGUCUCCACUGACGACGGACAGAGGAGAGACACCACUGGGAGCCACCCUGCCCUCCUGCUAUUGUGGAGGCCAACAAAGUUUUGAACCGAAAACCAAAAAAACAGAAACAAACAAACAAUAAAUUUAAACUAGAAAAAAAAUUUAUAUAUAUAUAUAAACAUAUAUAUAUAUAUAUAUAUAAAAGGGAAAGAAGAUGAGGACUCUUCAAGAAUAAGAUGGAACCGCGAGGCGGAGCCAAGCCCCUGCACCGGUGGUCCAGGCCCUUGUUCCCCAAGGCGGAUGGAAGGACGGAUGCUUCUUUCUCUUCACAAAUACCUCAUGGACGUUGUCUUUGGGAAAGCCGGAGGGGGCGGCUGGGGCAGGGCCUGUCCCUCGGCCAGGGCAGAUGGAAGCGGGUGGGCGGGGCUGAGAGAGGGUAUCAGGGACAGGGGUGAAGAGCCCCAAACUCCCCUCCCAAAUCAACUGAAAAAGCUUUAAAAAAAGACAGGAAAAAAAGGAGUAAGAAAGCAAAAAGAACAGAUGAAGGAAAACUUAACAACUUUUGGGUGGUUUGAUUCCUCCUUUGAUUUCUUUUUCGGUUCUCUUUUGUCUGACCUCUCUCCUCCCCUCCUUCCUCUCUCCUCCCCUCCUUCCUCUCUCCUCUCCUCCUUCCUGUCUCCUCUCUCUCCCUUUGCUCUCCUCUCUUCUCUCUCAAUCUUGUUCUUUCUGUGUCUCUCCUCAAACCAAAGUGUUGCAGUGAAGGACACGAGCCAUUGAAAUCAGGGUGGGGCCUGACAGCCGUAGUGUGGCCCCUGCCCCUUGUUGGGCAGGAGCAGAGAGAGAGGAGAGCCCUGAGACCGCAGGGCUUUGGCCUGGGCAGCUUCCACUUUCUGCCGGACACUCUGAGGAGAGGCAGAUGGAGCUCCAGGCCUCAGCGUUCUCUUUUUUCCUUGUCUCCCUUCUCCCACCCGGGAAAUGAAACUGUUGGGCUGGGCGACGGAGGCAGCAGAGACUCGGCCAUUGCAGGGGCCUCUGGGUGCCUUGUCCGGGCAGUGGUGAAGUAGCCGCCCCUCCCACCCCGGCACGAUGGGGCCUGGCACCUCGUCUACCCAACCUCACCGGAAUGUAAGCAUCUCCGCUGAACGACUCCCUGCCCUUACCCUACCUCUGAGUUUGUCCAUGUUUAUUUCCUGAAGAGAGAAGGGACUGGCAAGAGGGCUUGGGCCCCAGCCCAAGGGUGGAGAGGGGGCCAAGGGCUCCUGACCAAAUAGGAAGGACAUUUGAGCAGAGCAAAAUGAAAGGAAUUACAACCAAAAACCCCCUCCGAGAAGACAGGCAGCAUGGAAGGCAUGGUGGAGAUGACUCAAACAAAAACUAUGAUUCUAGACCAAAAAGGAAAAAAAAAAAAAAAAAAGGAAAGAAAAUCCAGGACUCACCACCACCCACUUCAUCCUGCUUCCUCCCCAUCAAGUCCCACCACCUGGGACCUCUCCCCACCCCAGUAUGUGGGAGUGGGGUAAAGAGGAGAGGAGGAGCAGGGGGCAGGGAUGGGGCAGAUGCCCUGAUGUUGGUGGAGGGACCCCUGUGCAGCCGGGGGUGCUGGGGACCCUCCCCAUCCAACCCUCACACCUAGGAAAAGAAAAACAAGAAAAAAAAAUUCCUGGGAGGGGGAAAAAUAACCAAAUCCCAAGCUUUAACUACAGCUGUGAAACCAAAUAUUGGGAAGGGGGUAGGAGGGAGGGAGGGGCAGGUGAGCCCCAGGUCUCCCCCUGGGCCCCCCUCCCCUGAGGACUCGAGAUAAGGCACCAAAUACCUCAUAGAACUUUAAUGUUAAAAAAAGGAAACCAAAUAUCGUUGGCUGGGGGCCAGCCAGGGCAAGGGGCUGGGGGGCUGGAGGGAGCCAGGGUUGGGAAGGUGAUGGGGGAAUUCAUGCCCCCCACCCCCAUCUGCCCCUUACACUCUGGUCCCCCGUCUCGACUCCGGGAAACAAAACUAUCUCAUCGUUUUUAUUUUGUGGUCUGUACAGAGCCUGUGUCCGUGUGUCUGUGUAUGAGCGAGAGAGUUGGAGGGCUGGGGAGCUUUAUGUGGGGGAUGGGGAGGGCAACCCCAGGCUAGGCUAUGGGCUAGGUUAGAUGUCCGAGGUUGGGGGCCAAGGGCCUGGGCUAGAAAGAGAGGAGAGAUGAGUGGGUUGGAGCAGUGGGGAGCCCUCUGAAUUUCUCUUCUCCCCAACCCUGACCUCCUACUUAAGGGAGGGACAGAGACUGGGUCUACCCUAAUGGUGGGCCUUUUCAUUGUGCCAAAAAAAAAAAAAAAAAAAUUGAUGCCAGUAACUAAACCACCUCUCUCUGUUCUCUUCUGGGGGGUGGGGUGGGUGUGUGUGUGGGGGUGGGUAGGGAUGGGGAACCCAAGCCCCAGUAGGAGUUGGGGCUGAGAUCAGGAGGAGGGGAAGGAUAUGAGUUUUCCAUCCAUCUCCCUGGAGAAGGCCAUGACGGGCUCUCCAAGCCCUGGGGAGAUCUGGCGAGGGACUAGCCAAGUCAGGGUGACCUCUUGACCUGACUAGUUUUUCUAACCCACAUGAACACCAGGGUGCCUCUCUCUUCCUCUAGCCCAGGGUAGGGGGACCUGAGUGAGAGAGAGAGUGAGACAGACAGCAAGAUUGAGACACGCGGGCCCCCACUGGUCUCUGAGUGGGAAAGGCAAGUGCGAGAGAUAAAGGCCUCCAAGAGAAAAAAGAAACAAACCAAAGAUUUAACCAUUUAAAAAAAAAAAAAAACCCACAGACAACUCCGCUACCUUUUUAUAUGUUGGAAAAAAAGUGAAAAAAAAUUAAAAAUAAAAAUAAAAAAAAAUACACAAAAACUCCAAGCCGCAAGUCCUUCAUGCGGUUUAAACUUUGACCUCAGCAGUCUCCAAAGCAAGACGACGAUGACAAAGGCGGAAACAAAGAAAAAAUAAUGUAUAUUUUUAAGUAUUUGUCCUUGAAUUGUUAGCUCCUUGUUAAACAAACAAAAGGAGAGAAAAAUCCAGAGAGAAGUGUUGCUGGGAUGGAGACAACUAUUUACUAUGUCUGUGACCCCUCCCUUCUGCCUCCCUCCCCUUCCUCUCUUUCCUGUCCUCUAUCCUUGCUGCCCCUCCCCCAAUAUGUCCCCCAAACCCAGGGGCUCAGUAUUUAUUUAUUUAUAUAAUUGCAGGGUGACUGGGGGCCUCUCUCGGCAACUCGUAGAGAGCCUUUGGAUAAUGGCAGGGUGGGGAAUGGGCGAGGAGUCUUUGGGAAGAGCAGGGGCCUGAACUUUCAACUCCUUUCUGGCCUCUUGUCCCACUGCUUCCACCAUCACCUUCCAAAUCCAGGGCUGCACUAGGGCAAGGUGACCACCCUACUUGGUAAAGACCUGAUUGGCGCAGCCCAUUCUGGUGUGGGUGUCUUUCACCACCCAGAAUGACCAGGUUGGAAUGGGGGUGGGUGAAGUUGGAGGGGGUGGCAAGUACAAGGCAAGGGUGCCCAGGAACCGGCAUCCAGAAAUCAGCCCUGGAGUAGACCUGCCUUUCCUCCAUCCUUACCAAGUUAGCCUCCCUUUCAGUUCCGUCUGACCCCUGUGUUGGUAGCCCCUUCCUUCCCUUCCUGUACCCCCUCCGUCUCUUCUCGUGGUAGCGGGUUAGUGUUUCAGUGUUCUUAACUCCAAUCUGCUUGUUCAUUGUACAAUGUGCUUCUUUUAAGGCCCCAUUUUUGUAACUUGAGUGUGUCAUUCAUCUGAACAACAAACAUCAAAAAAUAAAAAAUUAAAAACUGUACAGAGAGAAAUGA